GCGGAUUUCGGCGGCGGAAACAUGGCGGUCGCGGCCGGGCCGGUAACGGAGAAAGUUUACGCCGACACUGGCCUGUAUUAGCGCGUAUGGCCUCGGGCCCUCGUUCCCCAAGGCGUGCCGCCUCCCUGUUCUCAGUCGCAGGCUGAAGCCUUGUCUGCUCUCCUCCUUUUUGGUUUGGUUUUGGAACUGACUCCGAGGGUUGGGAGAGCGCGUUGGUGGCGACGGCCGAGUCAGGUAGGGAGAAAUGGGUGGACGGCAGGGCGGCGAGAUCUAGGCAUAGACACUGCCAGGGCUCCGCGUGGUCCGGACCCCAAGCUCCGCCCAGUCGGCCUCCCAGGGCCGGGGUAGGAUACCUGCCUCUGGAGGAGUUGACAGUGGUGGUUGGAGAUUGGAGGGUGUGGGAGCGCCUCUCCGUAUUUCGCAAGGGUUCCCCCUCAACUGGGCGCCACGUUGUGGUCGCGUUCUCCGAGGCAGAGGAUGGUGGAGAACAGCCAAGCUCCUUGUCGGACCUCCCACAUCUCGCUAGAAGGAGGCCGAAAGGGAGAGAAAUUGCUGUUGCUGCUCUAGUGCUGAGGAGUUUGAUAUUCUAGAUGACAUUUUCCUCGUAUGAGAUGGCUCAAAGAGUUAUCAGUAAUUCAGAACUGAAGCACUGAAAUUCCCUGUUUUUUCAGUGUAGUUCUUUCAGCCUUGACACUUCUAGAUGGGACAGAGUUUCUGAGUGAAAGAUAAUGCAAGUGAUACGGUAUGCCUCAAGCCAUUCCCUAGAGGUAGGACAUGGAGAGAGAAUUGGUUUGGAAGAAUUUGGGUGAAUUAAGUAAAGACUGGUGGAAAGCUGAAAUAGAAACCAAACAUUCAUGGACUCUCCCUUAGUUCUACUAGUUAUUAGUUGUGGGAUAUAGCUAAGUUCUGUAUUCUCUUUAGGCAUUAGUAAGUGUCCAAUGGUGACUAUUGUUGUUAAAUGUAGUUAUUUCUUUAUUAGUCUUUAUUUUUCAACAAGUAUUUAUUGAAUACCUUCUUGAUGCCGGAUUUUUGCUAGUCACUGGGUGUACAGUAUUGAAGACAAACCCUCAGAGACCUUUUGAUCUAGUGGGAAAUGCAGACAUGAAAUAAGUGAUGGCUGUCUUUUGAAGAAGAUCAGAAUGGGGAAGAGUUUUGUAAAUUAGCCAUUUAAAAACAAUCUGCCAUGUUGAUUUUGGUCCAUAGGAAGAUCACUAUAAACAAAAUUUCCACAAGAGAAAAUGUUGAAAUAGGAGUUGCGGAUACAUUGGAUAUACUGGAUGAAAUACAAGCGGUUAAUUUUUGUAACGUGAGGGAAAAGCCCACAUUGCUGGUUACAUGUGUAAAUCACUGCGUUAUUGCUUUAGUCAUUGUCUCUAUUUAGCAAUGACAAGACUGGAAGAAGUAAAUAGAGAAGUGAACAUGCAUUCUUCAGUGCGGUAUCUUGGCUAUUUAGCCAGAAUCAAUUUAUUGGUUGCUAUAUGCUUAGGUCUAUACGUAAGAUGGGAAAAAACAGCAAAUUCCUUAAUUUUGGUAAUUUUUAUUCUUGGUCUUUUUGUUCUUGGAAUCGCCAGCAUACUCUAUUACUAUUUUUCAAUGGAAGCAGCAAGUUUAAGUCUCUCCAAUCUUUGGUUUGGAUUCUUGCUUGGCCUCCUAUGUUUUCUUGAUAAUUCAUCCUUUAAAAAUGAUGUAAAAGAAGAAUCAACCAAAUAUUUGCUUCUAACAUCCAUAGUGUUAAGGAUAUUGUGCUCUCUGGUGGAGAGAAUUUCUGGUUAUGUCCGUCAUCGGCCCACUUUACUAACCACAGUUGAAUUUCUGGAGCUUGUUGGAUUUGCCAUUGCCAGCACAACUAUGUUGGUGGAGAAGUCUCUGAGUGUCAUUUUGCUUGUUGUAGCUCUGGCUAUGCUGAUUAUUGAUCUGAGAAUGAAAUCUUUCUUAGCUAUUCCAAACUUAGUUAUUUUUGCAGUUUUGUUAUUUUUUUCCUCAUUGGAAACUCCCAAAAAUCCGAUUGCUUUUGCGUGUUUUUUUAUUUGCCUGAUAACUGAUCCUUUCCUUGACAUUUAUUUUAGUGGACUUUCAGUAACUGAAAGAUGGAAACCCUUUUUGUACCGUGGAAGAAUUUGCAGAAGACUUUCAGUCGUUUUUGCUGGAAUGAUUGAGCUUACAUUUUUUAUUCUUUCCGCAUUCAAACUUAGAGACACUCACCUCUGGUAUUUUGUAAUACCUGGCUUUUCCAUUUUUGGAAUUUUCUGGAUGAUUUGUCAUAUUAUUUUUCUUUUAACUCUUUGGGGAUUCCAUACCAAAUUAAAUGACUGCCAUAAAGUAUAUUUUACUCACAGGACAGAUUACAAUAGCCUUGAUAGAAUCAUGGCAUCCAAAGGGAUGCGCCAUUUUUGCUUGAUUUCAGAGCAGUUGGUGUUCUUUAGUCUUCUUGCAACAGCGAUUUUGGGAGCAGUUUCCUGGCAGCCAACAAAUGGAAUUUUCUUGAGCAUGUUUCUAAUCGUUUUGCCAUUGGAAUCCAUGGCUCAUGGGCUCUUCCAUGAAUUGGGUAACUGUUUAGGAGGAACAUCUGUUGGAUAUGCUAUUGUGAUUCCCACCAACUUCUGCAGUCCUGAUGGUCAGCCAACACUGCUUCCCCCAGAACAUGUACAGGAGUUAAAUUUGAGGUCUACUGGCAUGCUCAAUGCUAUCCAAAGAUUUUUUGCAUAUCAUAUGAUUGAGACCUAUGGAUGUGACUAUUCCACAAGUGGACUGUCAUUUGAUACUCUGCAUUCCAAACUAAAAGCUUUCCUCGAACUUCGGACAGUGGAUGGACCCAGACAUGAUACGUAUAUUUUGUAUUACAGUGGGCACACCCAUGGUACAGGAGAGUGGGCUCUAGCAGGUGGAGAUACACUACGCCUUGACACACUUAUAGAAUGGUGGAGAGAAAAGAAUGGUUCCUUUUGUUCCCGGCUUAUUAUCGUAUUAGACAGCGAAAAUUCAACCCCUUGGGUGAAAGAAGUGAGGAAAAUUAAUGACCAGUAUAUUGCAGUGCAAGGAGCAGAGUUGAUAAAAACAGUAGAUAUUGAAGAAGCUGACCCGCCACAGCUAGGUGACUUUACAAAAGACUGGGUAGAAUAUAACUGCAACUCCAGUAAUAACAUCUGCUGGACUGAAAAGGGACGCACAGUGAAAGCAGUAUAUGGUGUGUCAAAACGGUGGAGUGACUACACUCUGCAUUUGCCAACGGGAAGCGAUGUGGCCAAGCACUGGAUGUUACACUUUCCUCGUAUUACAUAUCCCCUAGUGCAUUUGGCAAAUUGGUUAUGCGGUCUGAACCUUUUUUGGAUCUGCAAAACUUGUUUUAGGUGCUUGAAAAGAUUAAAAAUGAGUUGGUUUCUUCCUACUGUGCUGGACACAGGACAAGGCUUCAAACUUGUCAAAUCUUAAUUUGGACCCCAAAGCGGGAUAUUAAUAAGCACUCAUACUACCAAUUAUCACUAACUUGCCAUUUUUUGUAUGCUGUAUUUUUAUUUGUGGAAAAUACCUUGCUACUUCUGUAGCUGCUCUCACUUUGUCUUUUCUUAAGUAAUUAUGGUAUAUAUAAGGCGUUGGGAAAAAACAUUUUAUAAUGAAAGUAUGUAGGGAGUCAAAUGCUUACUGUAAAUGCAUAAGAGACGUUAAAAAUAACACUGCACUUUCAGGAAUGUUUGCUUAUGGUCCUGAUUAGAAAGAAACAGUUGUCUAUGCUCUGCAAUGGUCAAUGAUGAAUUACUAAUGCCUUAUUUUCUAGGCAUAUAAUAAUAGUUUAGAGAAUGUAGACCAGAUAAAUUUGUUUACUGUUUUAAGAAAACUACCAGUUUACUUACAGAAGAUUCUUUUUUCCAAACAGUAGGUUUCAUCCAAGACCAUUUGAAGAACUGCAAACUCUUUCUCUUAGAAAAGAAAGAGGGCAGCCUAAAAUAAACGCAAAAUUUGCUUAUACUCCAUCACAUUCAGAUGUCUUGGUUGUGACUUAUUACCAGUGUGGCAGAGAACCCAAGUUACAUUUUAGAUCAAAAUAUUCUUUAUGUAGGUAUUGUUAAAAGGCUAGAGCCUACAAGUUGCUCUUCCAUGCGUUGGUCAGGGGGCCCUGAAAACACUGGUAAUAUUAAGAGUCUUUCUCAGGGUAACUUAAUGUUUUCUUAAUGAACAGUGUUUCCAGCUACAAAUUCUUCCAAUAAAUUGUCUUCCUUUUUGAAAAGUACUCUCAUAGAAGAAAUUUAGCAAUUUCUCGUUGACUGACUCAGUCUAUUUUAAGUAUUCAGAAAAGAUUUUGAUCCCCAUUGAGUUAAUGCUCUGCCUUGAAAAUUAUUUUUCUGAUCCUUGUUAGUGAUAACAUUUUUUUUCUACUGAAGGUCAGAGGAUAGGAAACAAGUAUUUCUCUUCUGGUAUACAUGUAAUGUAUUCUGUAAAAAAGUAUUCAUAUUGGCAAUUUUAGUUAGGCAUAAUAUUGUGGUUGUAAUUUUUAAAACUUAGUGUUUUGUCUGAUUAAAGCAGGCACUGAUCAGGGUAUCUCCUAAGAGGUAAUUCACUUCUUAUUCCUUUCCAAUAAUUAUUACAUUCUAAAUUUUCAUCUAUGAGAAAUAACAAACAAGAAGGGAAUAGAAUUAAAUUGGGGUAUAAUCUAAUCUUCAUUGUUUAAAUGGUUUGCCUUCUCACCAUUGAAGCCAUUUUUUUAUAGCCUCAGAAAGAGGAAAUAAUGCCUCCACCAUUUUCUACCUGGUGACUUGAAAAUUGAACUUUUAAGUUAGGAAGAAGUUAGAGUCAGGGAACUUGUAUACCACUAUCUAUGCAGCAUUGUUAUAGUCUGAUUAUUUCUGUGUUUUGAAUAUGAUUUUCCUAAUGCUCUAAAUAAAAUUUUGUUAAAAAUUAAUUUUUUAUUUAAUGAUGUGCAAAUAUUGAAUAUUUUAGUAUAUUUAUUAAAAGUGGUAGUCAUUAAAAAUGCCCAUGUUUUAGAGUUCAUGUUUGGAAGUUUCCAUUAUAGGUUAAGGAUUUAUAUUAGUAUUGUCCAAAUAAAAUAGUAUAGUUUUUUUUAUUGCUCUGUUCAGCAGUAGGGUAGUAGAAAAGCCAAAUGUUAAAAUUAUGAGCUUUUAGCUUAAAAAAAGUUAAUGUUAAGUAAAAUCUCCUUUUAAAUUUCUCAGCUAUUUGUGAGCAGGUUAGCUUUAAAGCAUUAUCUCUUCACUUUAAGAAAGCCAAAUACAAAAGUAUAUUCUGCAUUCUUUAUAAGGUAGUAUUAAGGUGGUACUAAAAAUUACAUUUUAAAAACAGCUGACAGUUUGACAGCCACAAACCUAACUUUUUCAUAUGUAUUUCCUGUGAAAGUAAAACCAAAAAUGGUCUUUGGGCCAAGAAUGUGACUUGAGCCAAUUUGUUAACCAAAAAUUUAUAGAAUGUCCACUUUGAUGAAUUCUCCUACCCAAACAAACAAAAAACAAUAAAUGACUUUUUGGGAUGGUAUCACAAAGCUAACAUUUUAAAAACAAUAACUAGGCCGGGUGCAGUGGCUCACGCCUGUAAUCCCAGCACUUUGGGAGGCCUAGGUGGGUGGAUCACUUGAGGCCAGGAGUUUGAGACCAGCCUGGCCAACAUGGGGAAACCUCAUCGCUACUAAAAAUACAAAAAAAAUUAUUAGCCGGGCAUGGUGGCAGGUGCCUGUAAUCCCAGCUACUUGGGAGGCUAAGGCACAAGAAUCGCUUGAACCCGGGAGGCAGAGGUUGCAGUGAGCUGAGAUUGUGCCACUGCACUCCAGCCUGGGCGACAGAGCAGGACUCUUUCUUUGUCUCAAAAAAAAAAAAAAGUACAUGUUUAGCCAGGCAUGGUGGCUCAUGCCUGUAAUCCCAGCACUUUGGGAGGCCGAGGCAGGUGGAUCAAAAGGUCAAGAGAUGGAGACCAUCUGGCCAACAUGGUGAAACCCCAUCUCUACUAAAAAUAAAAAAAUCAGCUGGGCGUGGUGGUGCACGCCUGUAGUCCCAUCUACUUGGGAGACUGAGGCAGGAGAAUCUCUUGAACCGGGGAGGCAGAGGUUGCAGUGAGCCGAGAUUGCGCCACUGCACUCCAGCCUGGCAACAGAGAGAGACUCCAUCUCAAAAAAAAAAAGAAACAAACAAAAAAAAUAAUAAGGGUGUAGAAAAGAAAUAUUACAAGAAGAAUAAAGUGAUUGGUUACUUUCACCUAAAGAUUGAAAAAUAGAUCUGACAAUGAGACUAAUUUGUCUAUGGCUGUCAUGUUUAAGAAAGAGUUGCUUGGAGUGAAAGGAAUUAUUUUAGGGCAAAACUUUACCAUUCUACUAAAAAGAGGUAACAUGGAGAUUUUUUCAACAUAACUUUGUUUAGUAUUUGUUUCCUCAUGUGAUACCUUGCUAAAACCACAAAACCACUAGCUCUAAAAACAUCAUCUUUUUUUUCAAUAGAAUAAAAAAAACAGUAUGAAUUUAUUUUCUUUUUUUAACCAUUAUUUAUUUAUUUUAAUUUUAUUAUUAUUAUACUUUAAGUUUUAGGGUACAUGUGCAAAUAGCAUACACACUGUUGCAAAAUAAAUAAGGAGCCAAGUUCUUUCUCUCCCCAUGACUUUUCAGUUAUGCCAUCAUUUUAUUCAAAAAUUUUUAGUUUGCUCUGAUCUAAACUCUUCCCUGGGAAACUUGGGGUUAUAUUUCCAUAGAAUUCUGUCUUGCUCUUAAUAAAUUCAAAAUUCUUUGGAAAAGAUGCAUUUCAGAGGAUUAUUCUUAUGACCAGUUAUGCUUUAAAAAAAUUAAAGUCUUAAUUAAAAUGCACUUAUAUUUAAUGCAUUAGUGGGUAGAUUUUUGUUUUGAGUAAAAUCUUUAUUAGAAUCUAUUUGUAACUGGAUAUUUUGUAAUUUUGGGCUCAAACAUAUUUACUCUUGGGUACUGCUUUUUUAUAUGUAUUCAAAUUUAUAGCUUAGUCUCUUUUAAAGUAAUAUUCUACAUUACUUUCCCACAAGUGAUGAUAGUUAAUAUAAUGUAUGCCAGAAGAAAAUGAUUUAAUUUUAAGAAUGUGAUUAGAUAUAUUUGACAGUAAGUGCUCAAAGGAGUUAGAUCUGUCAGUACUUUCGAAUGUCUCCUGUAUUGGAAACUAUUAGACUGUCACCUCUUUUUAGGCAGAGGCUUACACAUGUUGGUAUUUCUGGUACACAGUUACCGAGAAGAGUGCCUUGUCCGUAAUGAGAAGCAUUUAAUAAAUAUUUUGGACUGAGUGAAUAAAUCUAGAAUCCUAAGGAGAAAUUGGAAUAACUUGAUUGUAAAUUACUACAUUUUCUUUAGUUUUACUUAAAUGGAUAUUAUUUCAAGAUCUUCAUUAAGCAAGUAAUUUAGUAAAAAACUUACAGAAUCCAUAAAAAGAAAGCAAAUCUCAAAUUUGUAGUUAAGAGUAAUAAGUGUUAAGAUUAGGGAAGGAAAAACUGUUUCAGAACUGGUUUGAAUGAAAACAUAGCUGAUGUUGCCAAAAAAUGGCUUUUUGUGAGUUGAGUCCAUUUCCAUCAUGACUCUAAUAUCAUUAAGAUUGAAUCAUUCAUUUCCUCACUAUUAUAUCUAGACAGAUUGGAAAUUUACCAGAAAUGGAAAUUAUUAAAAGUCUGACUGAUGAACAAAGAAGGAAUUUGACUAUGCAUAUCAGUGACAACUAAAUUGGAAGGUCAGUAAAAUAGGCCUAUAAGCAUAAGCAGGUUAAGGACAAGCUAGGGAAACUAUAAGUAUCUCCUUUUUUAUAUUGUCUUACCUAUUCACUAAUUAUAACACAUAGAAACAAUAUAAAACGAUGAAGUUUAAGCAGUAAUUGUUUUGAGAAACCAUUCUGUUGAUAAUUUACAUUUAUGUUUAUUAGGAAAUAUUGUUAUUAUUACUUAGACCAAAGUUGACUGAAAAUUGAAAACUGUGGGCUACCCGUAAGGUUUUUUGCUUUGAAAUAUUCAAUACCUAAAAGCCAUUUUGAUUUUAAAAAUGAAGUUGACCAGUCAUCUUGUAUGAUGACCUCAUAAUAUUUUAUAAGUUUGAACUUAAAAUAGUUAGAAGUAGACAGUUUUAGUAAGCUUUUGUUUUUAUUUGGUCUAGCCUAAAAGACAUUGAUUUAUCUCAAAGAUUUUUAGCAGUGUGCAAGGGACAAAUGAGUAUGACAUAGCUUCCUAGACAAGCAGUGUUCACUCAAUGCCAAGUAAACUUUUCUAAGUUCAAAAAUAUUUUUAUAUUAAAACACAUACCAAUGUAUUGAUGAACAAAA